GUUCCUCCGACUUCCGGACAUCUCCCUGGGAGUCGCGCAGAGUGGAGUCAAAGGCAACCAGUGCUCGCUGCGGUCUCUGGGGAUCGGGACCGCGGCGGCGGCCCGCGAGCGGGAUGUUCCGGGGCUUGAGCAGUUGGUUGGGCUUGCAGCAGCCGGUGGCAGGCGGUGGGCAGCCCAAUGGAGAUGCUCCACCCGAGCAGCCGUCCGAGACGGUGGCUGAGUCUGCGGAGGAGGAGCUGCAGCAAGCGGGAGACCAGGAGCUCCUCCACCAGGCCAAAGACUUCGGCAACUAUUUAUUUAACUUUGCAUCUGCUGCCACAAAAAAGAUAACUGAAUCAGUUGCUGAAACAGCACAAACAAUAAAGAAAUCCGUAGAAGAAGGAAAAAUAGAUGGCAUCAUUGACAAGACAAUUAUAGGAGAUUUUCAGAAGGAACAGAAAAAAUUUGUUGAAGAGCAACAUACAAAGAAGUCAGAAGCAGCUGUGCCCCCAUGGGUUGACACUAACGAUGAAGAAACAAUUCAACAACAAAUUUUGGCCUUAUCAGCUGACAAGAGGAAUUUCCUUCGUGACCCUCCGGCUGGCGUGCAAUUUAAUUUCGACUUUGAUCAGAUGUACCCCGUGGCCCUGGUCAUGCUCCAGGAGGAUGAGCUGCUAAGCAAGAUGAGAUUUGCCCUCGUUCCUAAACUUGUGAAGGAAGAAGUGUUCUGGAGGAACUACUUUUACCGCGUCUCCCUGAUUAAGCAGUCAGCCCAGCUCACGGCCCUGGCUGCCCAACAGCAGGCCGCAGGGAAGGAGGAGAAGAGCAAUGGCAGAGAGCAAGAUUUGCCGCUGGCAGAGGCAGUACGGCCCAAAACGCCACCCGUUGUAAUCAAAUCUCAGCUUAAAACUCAAGAGGAUGAGGAAGAAAUUUCUACUAGCCCAGGUGUUUCUGAGUUUGUCAGUGAUGCCUUCGAUGCCUGUAACCUAAAUCAGGAAGAUCUAAGGAAAGAAAUGGAGCAACUAGUGCUUGACAAAAAGCAAGAGGAGACAGCCGUACUGGAAGAGGAUUCUGCAGAUUGGGAAAAAGAACUGCAGCAGGAACUUCAAGAAUAUGAAGUGGUGACAGAAUCUGAAAAACGAGAUGAAAACUGGGAUAAGGAAAUAGAGAAAAUGCUUCAAGAGGAAAAUUAGCUGUUCCUGAAAUAGAAGAAUAAUCCUUAACAGUCUGCAAACUGACAUUAAAUUCUAGAUGUUGACAAUUACUGAAUCAGAAGGCAUGAAAGAGUAUAAUUUUAUGAAAUUCAAAAUUAUUCUUUUUUCAAGUUGAAACUUGCCUCUUCUACUUUAAAAAAGUAUAUAGAACAGUUACUUCUAAUAAUCAGAAAGAGAUGUUUUAUAGAACAUUUCUUUAAUAUAAAGUUAGAGAUGUCUUCAUAGGCAGUAUGGCUAUCUUUGCCACAGAAACAUAAGUAAAAUUUUAGAGUUCUGUUUUCCAUGAGGUCAAAAAUAUAAUUUAUUCCUCAGUCAUGGUUUUCUAAAUAUCUGUACUCCACAUUCCAUUUUAAUUGAUAUGAGGGUGUUAAAGUACCUACUUAAUGGGUUGAUUACUAUCAAAAUGACCAAAUUAUACCAAAGAACUUAAGAGGAAGCACUUUCAGAACUAUUCACUUGCCAGGUAUUUUCUAAAAUUCCACCUGAAAGCCAAAAGAUAAAAUAAAUAAGUUGAUUUUAAUGAUAUAAGCAUCACACAAUUUUACAUUAAGAAAUACUGUGCAGGCCAUGCGUGGUGGCUCAGGCCUGUAAUCCCAGCACUUUGGGAGGCCGAGGUGGGCAGAUCACCGGAGGUCAGGAGUUCGAGACCAGCCUUGCCAACAUAGUGAAACCCUGUCUCUACUAAAAAUACAAAAAUUAGCCGGGCAUGGUGGCAGGCACCUGUAAUCCCAGCUACUAGGGAGGCUUUUGAACCCAGGAGGCAGAGGUUGCAGCGAGCUGAGAUCGCGCCACUGCACUCCAGCCUGGGUGAUAGAGUGAGAUUCAGUCUCAAAAAAAAAAAAAAAAAAAAGCUGUGCGAAAAUAUUUGUUUUUCUCUGGGGCCUUUUCUUUCUUUUCUUUUUAAACUAUACCAGAAAUUUUACAUCACAGUUUUUAUACAAAGUGGGACCUUCCAUACUUUUUGUAUUACAAUAACCUUCAGAAGCCCAUUCCCCUUAAAGUCUGUUGUUCUUGUUUUAAUCAUCACCACAUAUAAAUGUUUUAGCUUUGUCUUAAACUGUGAGUCUUCAUAAAAUUGUGUUCCUCCGAGUUCACCUUCUAGGACUUUAUUGAUUAAUCCUUCUCUUUCUGCUAUACCAGCAGACACAUAUUCAUAGAAUAUGAUUAUUUUUAAAGAACAAGGUGAGGAGGCUGAGGCAGGAGAAUUGCUUGAACCUGGGAGAUGGAGGUUGCAGUGAGCUGAGAUCACGCCACUGCACUCCAGCCUGGGUGACAGAGUGAGAGACUCCGUCUCAAAAAUGAAUGAAUGAAUGAAUGAAUGAAUGAACGAACGAACAAGGUGGUUUAAUGUCAGAAAACUUCCUAAGCAUUUGCUCCCCAAACCUUUCAUGUUUUUCAAGAAGCCUUUAUUACAUAAAGGGGAAUAGAAUUAAAAUGUUUCUUUAUAAGAAAAAUAUACAUAUUUGUGUUCUUGGCCCCAUUAAAACUAGUCAGUAGUCCUUUGGCAAAGAUAUAGUCAACAAGAGAACUGGGUAUGAGUCCAGGCAUUACUCCUGUUCAUAGUUGUGGAUGCAUGUGUCUGAGCCAGACUGUCUCAACUGGAGUCUCUUGGGUUAUAGCAGUAAACCCGUGUAUUCCAUGAAACCACUGGGCCCAUCAUCAAAAGGUUUCCACUUGUGGUGCCACAGUUGCUUAUUACUGAGUUUGGGUUCCAAGAUGACUGGCAACUUCUGAAAUAAUCUCAUUGAAGGAAAGAGUUUCAUUUUUUUUUUAAAAGAGUUUGCUGGAGGAAAAGAAGCAUGUUAAAUGUUUUUAAGCAGCUAAAAGUCCUAGAUGGAAGCAUAUCAGGAUGUGUCGGUGCUUGGCUCUUAGUGAAUGCACUAAAAUUCUUAUUGAUAAAUGUUGAAUAAACACACACAAAAAAGUAUCAGAGAAAGAGAAAAACCCUACAAUGGCAAUAGAGGUGUGUGACAGUUAUUGCUAUCAAUUUUACAUAAUAUCUCAUUUAAAAACAACCUAAUUAUGCAUUGCCUGUGAAAAUAAAAGGAUAAAAUAAGAUUUUGUACAUACUGUAAGAAUACAGUUGUGCUGUAUUUUUAUGGAUUCAUCAAGGAGUAAAAUGUUCUGCUUUAGUAAAUUAUAUAGGUAACUGAAGUGUUAUUCCUUUAAAGAGCAAAAUAAUUUAUCACCAUGUUUGGUGGAAAAUUUCUAAGUAUUUAUUACAUGCCUAGGGGUUAGCCAACAAGAUAUACCAAGCAUGAAAACCUGUAAAACUUAAUAAAAUGCUAAAAUAUGAACAUCACACUAUGGAGAUUAUGCCUCACUACUCAAAGAGUGUGGCUCAGGAACCAGUGUAGCUUGGCCAUGCCCUGGCAGUAUGUUGGAAAUGCCUGCCCCAGACCAGUUGAUGUUACUAAGAACGCCCAGGGGAUGAGAAUGGACUUUAUUUACAGUUUGGGAAGCACUGGUCUAAUAUGCUCUCAGGGAAGCUGAGGUUUCUACUGCUUUUUACUUUUUACCCUUCCACUAGAUGUCCUUUGCAGCAGUGUUUUUCUAGUUGGCAUUACAGGUGUCUCCUCUGAGGUUCCAGUUAUUUCUAUACUACCAAAAUUAAAAAGACCCAAGGGCUGGGCAUGGUGGUUCACACCUGUAAUCCCAGCACUUUGGGAGGCUGAGGCAGGCAGAUUGCUUGAGCUCAGGAGUUCAAGACCAGCCUGGGCAACAUAGGGAGACCCCUGCCUCUACAAAAAUACAAAUGAGCCAGGUGUGGUAGCCCACACCUGUGGUCCUAGCUACUUGGAAGGCUGAGGCAGGAGGAUCGCUUGAGCCCAGGAGAUCCAGGCUGCAGUAAGCCAUGAUCAUGCCACUGCACUUCAGCCUGGGUGACAGAGACUCUGUUUCAAAAAAGGGAGGGGGGGCAAGUUUUUAGGGGGAUGAGAAAUAUUCUUGGUAAAUCGGGCAUUUCUUUUUUUGUUUGUUUUUUUUUCUUGGAGACAGAAUCUUGCUCUGUCACCCAGGCUGGAGUGCAGUGGCUUGAUCUCAGCUCACGGCAACCUCCGCCUCCCAAGUUCAAGCGAUUCUCCCACCUCAGCCUCCAGAGUAGCUGGGAUUACAGGCAACCGCCACCAUGCCCAGCUAAUUUUUUUGUAUUUUUAGCAGAGAUGGGGUUUCACCGUGUUGGCCAGGCUGGUCUCAAGCUCCUGAUCUCAAAUGAUCCGCACGCCUUGACCUCCCAAAGUGUUGGGAUUACAGGCAUGAGCCACAGCCUUAAUUGGUAAUUUUUGAAAAAAAAACUAGAGAAACAUUGUUUCAGAGAUAAAGCAGCAAUUACACUUGUACUCCCAGUGAUUUAAGAUGCACUAUUGUAAUCAAGAUGAUUUGCUUUAAUCAAAAUAUUGUUAAAAAUAGGAUUUCAGGACAUUUAAAAGGUUUCAGCAGAAAUCUUAUGAUUAUGUCUGACUUGCAGUAUUUUAUUUGCCUCUUUGACGGCUUUUUUUUUUUUUUUUUUUUUGAGACAGAGUCUCACACUGUUGCCUGGGCUGGAAUGCAAUGGCGCAGUCUCAGCUCACUGCAAACCUCCGGCUCCCGGGUUCAGGCAGUUCUCCUGCCUCAGCCUCCCUAGUAGCUGGGAUUAUAGGCAUGUGCCACCACACCCGGCUAAUUUUUGUAUUUUUAGUAGAGACAGGGUUUCGCCAUGUUGGUCAGGCUGGUCUUGAACUCCCAACCUCAGGUGAUCCGCCCGCCUCGGCCUCCCAAAGUGCUGGGAUUACAGGCGUGAGCCACUGCGCCCAACCUUAAUGGCUUUUUGGUAUUAAAAACCAGGACUCUGAAUGUGCAUCAAUAAUUCAAAUAAUUUUAUAUAGUUACUCUUUCUAGUAAUAGAUACCCCCCUCCAUUUUUAAGUAAAGAUAAACAUUUUUUAAUUAGGAAAAUUAGGCACAUUUAAUUUUAGCAAAUUUAGUUUUUCAACUUUUUUUUUUUUCUUUUUUUUUUUUUUUGAGAUGGAGGCUCACUCUGUUGCCCUGGCUGGAGUGCAGUGGCCGCAACCUCGGCUCACUGCAACCUCCGCCUCCUGGGUUCAAGUGAUUCUCCUGCCUCAGCCUCCCGAGUAGCUGGGAUUACAGGCGUGUGCCACCACACCUGGCUAAUUUUUGUAUUUUUAGUAGAGACGGGGUUUCACCAUGUUGGCCAGGCUGGUCUUGAACGACUGGCCUCAGGUGAUCCGCCCACCUCGGCCUCUCAAAGUGCUGGGAUUACAGGCAUGAGCCACCAUGCCCAGCCAGUUUUUCAACUUUUAAAAAUAAAAGUGGUAGAAUUUUUUUUUUUCUUUUUGAGACAGGGUCUUGCUCUGUCACUCAGGCUAGAGUGCAGUGGUGGGAUCUCAGCUCACUGCAGCCUCCGCCUCCCAGGCUUAAGGGAUCCUCCCUCCUCAGCCUCCCGAGUAGCUGGGACCACAGGCAUGCACCACCACGCCUGGCUAAUUUUUGUAUUUUUUGUAGAGAUGGGUGUCUCCCCAUGUUGCUCAGGCUGUUCUUGAACUUCUGAGCUCAGGUGAUCUAUCUGCCUCGGCCUUCCAAAGUGCUGGGAUUACAGGCAUGAUGAGCCACUGCACCUGGCCAAAAGUGGCAGAAAUUUUGAUAUGGUUUAUAAUCAGUUUUAUUGUGGGGAAGAUGGGCCAUUUUAAUGAAUGAUUAUUUCUAUUGGCUAAACUACCGAGUCACGACAUGACAAAUACACAUGAAGCUUUAAUCACAUGCAGUUAUAUACUUCUCACAAAUCAUCAAAUUAUUUAUCUGGUCUUCACACUAAGGGAUUUACUUAGAUAAGCCAUCGAUGAUUUCAGUUGUUAAAAGUGUGGCUUUUUAAACAGCAUUUAUUCAGUGCAUCCUGAUUUAUUUCAAAAUGAAAAAUUGUUACCUUUUUUUCUGAAUAAAUAAAGCUUACUUUUAGUGGCAAGGUA